CUGACGACGUGCUGCGUCGUUACUUUUGAAACGCUUGGCGGGGAAGUGCUGUUGGAGCCGCUGUGGUUGCUGUCCGCGGAGUGGAAGCGCGUGCUUUUGUUUGUGUCCCUGGCCAUGGCGCUGCAGCUCUCCCGGGAGCAGGGAAUCACCCUGCGCGGGAGCGCCGAAAUCGUGGCCGAGUUCUUCUCAUUCGGCAUCAACAGCAUUUUAUAUCAGCGUGGCAUAUAUCCAUCUGAAACCUUUACUCGAGUGCAGAAAUACGGACUCACCUUGCUUGUAACUACUGAUCUUGAGCUCAUAAAAUACCUAAAUAAUGUGGUGGAACAACUGAAAGAUUGGUUAUACAAGUGUUCAGUUCAGAAACUGGUUGUAGUUAUCUCAAAUAUUGAAAGUGGUGAGGUCCUGGAAAGAUGGCAGUUUGAUAUUGAGUGUGACAAGACUGCAAAAGAUGACAGUGCACCCAGAGAAAAGUCUCAGAAAGCUAUCCAGGAUGAAAUCCGUUCAGUGAUCAGACAGAUCACAGCUACGGUGACAUUUCUGCCACUGUUGGAAGUUUCUUGUUCAUUUGAUCUGCUGAUUUAUACAGACAAAGAUUUGGUUGUACCUGAAAAAUGGGAAGAGUCGGGACCACAGUUUAUUACCAAUUCUGAGGAAGUCCGCCUUCGUUCAUUUACUACUACAAUCCACAAAGUAAAUAGCAUGGUGGCCUACAAAAUUCCUGUCAAUGACUGAGGAUGACAUGAGGAAAAUAAUGUAAUUGUAAUUUUGAAAUGUGGUUUUCCUGAAAUCAAGUCAUCUAUAGUUGAUAUGUUUUAUUUCAUUGGUUAAUUUUUACAUGGAGAAAACCAAAAUGAUACUUACUGAACUGUGUGUAAUUGUUCCUUUUAUUUUUUUGGUACCUAUUUGACUUACCAUGGAGUUAACAUCAUGAAUUUAUUGCACAUUGUUCAAAAGGAACCAGGAGGUUUUUUUGUCAACAUUGUGAUGUAUAUUCCUUUGAAGAUAGUAACUGUAGAUGGAAAAACUUGUGCUAUAAAGCUAGAUGCUUUCCUAAAUCAGAUGUUUUGGUCAAGUAGUUUGACUCAGUAUAGGUAGGGAGAUAUUUAAGUAUAAAAUACAACAAAGGAAGUCUAAAUAUUCAGAAUCUUUGUUAAGGUCCUGAAAGUAACUCAUAAUCUAUAAACAAUGAAAUAUUGCUGUAUAGCUCCUUUUGACCUUCAUUUCAUGUAUAGUUUUCCCUAUUGAAUCAGUUUCCAAUUAUUUGACUUUAAUUUAUGUAACUUGAACCUAUGAAGCAAUGGAUAUUUGUACUGUUUAAUGUUCUGUGAUACAGAACUCUUAAAAAUGUUUUUUCAUGUGUUUUAUAAAAUCAAGUUUUAAGUGAAAGUGAGGAAAUAAAGUUAAGUUUGUUUUAAAUUUGUCUUAAAACAUUUUGAUACUGGUUUGGUGUUGAUAUAGUUAAAUGGUAAUUAGAAUUGAUUCAGCAUAGCUAAUGAAUUCUUGUUCCUACGAAGUUAUAGAACUUAAGGGUCCAAAGUUGAGUGAGUCUUGAGGUGUCUUCAAUCUAAUGGAUAAACUUUGAUCACAUCCUGUUCAUCUCAUAGCAAUAGACUUAAGGCUAUUACUUCAUCAUUGUGAAAAGAUAAAUGUCCUUUGGAAUUAGUCCAACAAUUCCAGUUGAACAAGUGUUGAUUUUAGUACUUUACUAUACUCUUAGCCUUAUUGUCAGCCUACUUUUCCUUAUAUACUUAAAUACUAUGCUUAUUCCUGUGCUUUCAUUAAUACCCUCAUCUGGUACAUGCUUUCUAUCCAGUUCUCACCUGUUUUUCCAAGGUCAGUUUAAGGCAGAUUUGUAAAGUCUUCUCUAAUCUCUAAUCUAAAUCUGACCUCAUUUUGUAAAAAUUCAGUUUAUUAAUGUUUAUUAUUAGACACUAAGUUCUUUAUGUGUAUUAACUUAUUUAACCUUCACUAUUUUUAAGUAAUUGCACAUAGUCUGAAUCUGUUCAUUCAGAAAUUACAUAUUGAGCAAAUACUGUGGAUCAGUGGCAGUUUCUGGGUUCUCAGUGACAAAUUUGUAGACUCUUCAUAUCUUUAUGGAAUAAGUGGACCACUGGUGUUACCAACCUAGAUGAUUUCAAGAAAAGUGGCAAUUAAAUGCUUCAUUUGUAUUUUAACUAUUUGAGAAGUCAGACUAAAUUCUGCGAAAUCACUUUUCCCCCCCAAGAUGGAGUCUUAUUCUGUCGCCCAGGCUGGAGUACAGUGACGCAGCUCAGCUCACUACAGCCUCUGCCUCCCGGAUUCCAGCCAUUCUUCCGUCUCAGCCUCCUGAGUAGCUGGGAUUACAGGCACGUGCCACCACACCUGGCUAAUUUUUAUAUUUUUAGUAGAGAGAGGGUUUCACCAUGUUGGCCAGGCUAGUCUUGAACUCCUGACCUCAUGAUCUGCCCGCCUUGACCUCACAAAGCAUUGGGAUUACAGGCGUGAGCCACUGCGCCCGGCUGAAAUCACAUUUUUAAAGGUUGUGUGUAUACUCUGGUCAUUUCAACUCAGCUACCAAUAUUAACAGGAUUAAAUUCUUAGAUUUUUGUAUCAUUUGCAUGCUACUAUUUACUCUGAGGUUUCUGGAGAGCUAGUCAUGAUGAGUCAUUUUACCCCUUACAGAUUAUAUAAUCAAUUAAGAAAUACACAUUUUGGGCUGGGCGCAGUGGCUCGCGCCUGUAAUCCCAGCACUUUGGGAGGCCGAGGCAGGUGGAUCACGAGAUCAGGAGUUUGAGACCAGCCUGGCCAAGAUGGUCAAACCCCGUCUCUACUAAAAAUAUAAAAAUUAGCUGGGCGUGGUGGCGGGCGCAUCUCAGCUACUUGGGAGGCUGAGGCAGGAGAAAUCGCUUGAACCCAUGAGGUGGAGGUUGCGGUGAGCCAAGACCGUGCCACUGUACUCUAGCCUGGGCGACAGAGCAAGGCUCCAUCUCAAAAAAUAAUAAAUAAAAAAGAAAUACACAUUUUGGAGCUGAGUGGGAGCCAAACUAUGAGUUUUAUUGAGGUGAAGCUAUACUGGAAAAGCUUUGCCCUGUAGCUCCAAGUGGACUGUCCCAUCCUCUUUCUAGACCUUGAGGCUUACCUCAGGAGGAUGAUGUUUAAAUCAACAGCUGAAAGACUUGUGAGUGGUUUCUACACCAUGUUAAAGAGAAGGUUCUAAGACAGCAUGAUAGGCCUCUAGGCCUGGCCUGGACUCUGGCUCAGUGUUGCUUACCAUAUGUAGAGGAUGAACAGAGGUUAAGCCCAUCAAGGUCUGAAGUAGAGCCCAGGAGGAACUGAACUGUAUCUGGCUUUCAGGAUCCUUUUCCCAGUGUCAUCAAUCAGAGAAGUCAAACCUCUGUGAGAAUGCUUGUGCAGAGGUAUAACAGUCUCAUGUAUUGGUUGGCUUUUGCUGCACCUUUCUCAUUCUGUUGGAGGGACAUUGGUUAGUCAGGACUCUGAAGGCCAGCUUUUUCACACUGACCAAAGCAAGUGAAGGUCAAGCCUAACUUUAAUGGGACCAGGAAGUAUACUCCUCCCAUGGAGGUGGUGGGAAUGGCACCGAGAAGUUUGAUGACAGUUAUCUAAUGGACUAGAGGUUGGCAAACUUUCUGUAAAUGGCCAGGUAGUAAAUAGUUCUGCUUUUGAAGGCAUAUGGUCUCUUGCACCUACUCGAGGCUGAAAGCAGCUAUAGACAAUACAUAAAUGAAUGAGCGUGAGUGUGUUCCAAUAAGAAAAAAACAUGGCUGUUUGCUUCGGCCCCAGGGUUGUAGCUUACCAGUCCUGUAACAGAUCACAGUUUGCUCUUUUGGUCACAAAUACUUGAACCCCUCCCUAGUUCAGAGCAUUUGAUACCGUAAUAUUUAAAGCUCACUUGUAAAACAUCGUUUGUUGCCUCCAUCCAUAGUAUCUCAAACAGAAUGUCUCUCCCAAAUAUACCUAAAUUCCAUAUUCUCUGAAGCACAACCAGCUAUUUUCUUGACAUACUUCCUAACACACCCCACAGUUCACAAUUUGAUCUGAAAACUUGUUAAGGGAGGUUCUUUGGCAUGUGAUGCCAUAAAAAGAGAGGUAUGGGCUCUCCUUUAAAAAAGAGACCCUUUUUAUGAGACUCACAAUAGGAUAAAGAGCCCAUGCCUAUUUUUAAUCAUUUUUUCACUAUAUAGACAUGCAUGCUGAAAAAUGUUUUUAUUAGUAUAAUGCUAAUUAUACUGACUUCCUAUAUAUUUUAGCAUAUAGAUUCAAAGAUUAUUAGCACAAUAAGGUAGAUAACUUCAUAGACCAUUUCUUCAUCUUGUUUUCAUUUAGUAUGUAAAAUUUAUCUAAAAUUUACAUGAAAGAUCAGAAUAGCUAUGUAAUGCUACUUUGUAACUCUUAUAUUUUCCACCAGAUGUCACUAAUGCUGUAAUAUUCAAAUUAAGAUGACUUUCUUUUGGUUCUAAAGGCUGUAAGCUUAUUGGAAAAGCAAGGUUACUCAGCAUUGGAAUUCCUGGCAACAAAUAUAUAAAUACAUUAGGGGAAUAAACACUUAGCAUUUAUUAUUUACUAGUCACUUCACAUGAAUUUUUAUUUAAUUCUCAUGCUUUUGUGCACAAGUAAAACUGGGGGUCAAUGGGCAUGCAAAUUGUGUCGUGGUUUUUGAAGUUUAGUGGUCUCUCCUAUCCCUGGCCAAGGAAGUAUGCAAAUUGUAUUGUGGUUUUUGAAGUUUAGGUGAUCUCUUCCUUCUAUCCCUAGCCAAGGAAGUUCAUCCUGACUCCCCAACAAGCAUAUCAAAAGGAGUGUUUCGUCACCUUUUUCCUCUUACCCUUUACAUCCUUUUAGCAAUAAAGUGUUCAGAACAAACUGGUUUUCCUUUACUGUGCUUUGCAAAACUUAUUCAUGUUUUAUUGGGUGACUUUGUAUUUACACUUUCCUCAGAUAGUCUGUUGUCAGAUGACUUUGACCAAUGAUUGGGAGGAACCAAAUACAGAGGAUUUUAUCCUAUGCCUAAUCUAUAUUGUCUACAGAGUAAAUCAGGUAUGAAUUUGUGAACAGUAAUGAAACAAUUUUCCAACUAAUCAGAAGAAUUGUUUGUUAAGUAACCUUAAUUACUCAGUUUUUGGUGAAUUGUUUGCGGCUUAACUUGUAAAUAAUUUCUUAUUCUUUUUUUAAAUGUAUGAAAUAUUUCUAGUUAUUUUGUUCAAUGUGACUGAUAAAAGUUUAUAUUGGAAUA